GAUUUACAUGCAAAGGGAUCUAAAGGGUGCCAGGUAAGAAAUGCCCCAGCACUAGGCUGGCAGACCAAGGGCAGCCACAACCAUGGGCUGGGGAACAGCAGGUGGGUAGGAUGGGGCUGGAGGGCAGGACGGAUCCAGAGAGGCAAGGCCUCUGCCUCCAGCUUUAGGGAACAGACAUCCUCAAAGACAGCUGGGGUGUGGGGUCCUCUGCAGGGGUGAGGCACAGGAGGGCCAUCUGCAGGCAGCUGGGAGUUCAUGAGUAUUUGAAGCAGGGGAGGGGACAGGGGACAGAUGGGAUCUGCCUCUCAUGCAUCAGGCAUGGGGAGGGGCUCAGGAGGUCAGUGAGGGGUGGCCCUGGGUCCCCUGGGAGUCCGGGAGUCUCUGUGUGAGCAGGACUUGGCUGUGCGGUGGUUAGAGACAAGGGUGAUCCACCAGCUCCAUCCUCAUGCCUUGGUGAUUUCUUGGAAUGUCCCUGGGAGUUGGGUGCAGGUAGAGACUUUGUAGACCAUAGCUCCUGGCACUGUGCUGCCUGCCUGCCCCAUCCUGGCUGUGAGUUCGCUGUGAAUCCUACGGAAUCCUGGCUGUGAGUUCGCUGUGAAUCCUAUGGAAAGGGCUACCCCAAGGGGACAGGAGUCCAGCCUCCUACUCUUGGCACUGCCAUCAUGCAGCCAGGGGCCUUGGGCAGGUUUGUGGGCCUCAGUUUCCUCAUCUGGAAAAUGGAGCCAGCCCAGAGAAAGUGUUUCCUGGCCUCCCAGGCUCAGGAAAGGAGUACAGGAGACCCCACUGGGGCCUGGAGGGUUGAAGGUCCCCUGUAUGCUGCAGACCUUGGGGAUCAAGGGCUAAGGGCUGAAGUUUCCCUGUGUUCCAUGGACCUUGGGGAUUGAGGCCCAGGGCCCCAGUAGGGCUCAUGUCCUGGGCUGCUCAAGCCCUGACCUAGGGAGUGAUCCUGUGCACCAGAUCCUGCUCCAAGAUCUCCAUAGGGCAGUCCUGCUCUUCCCAGACCCCAGGCGGGCAAGUCACCAGUUUUGCAGACGGGGAAGUUGAGGCUGAGCCAGUUGCUGUCUGAGGACAAGAGCCCUCACUAUAGCAGAACCUGGCGGCUGAGAACACAGGAUGUGGCUUUUGGCAGAUGAAGUGUGAACCAAGACAAGACCUUGGUCGACCUCAGACAUAGCUAGACACAUGCCUCUUAUCAGAUACAUGAUUUGCAAGUAUUUUCUCCCUAUUGACGGUACUCACCCUUCUUGCGAUGAUGUGAGAUGAUAAAAUGCCUACAUGAUGAGAUGAAGUGAGAUGAAAAACAUAGGCCUUGUGAUGGAAUGGGAAAUUCCAGAGAUAAUUUGCACGUGCGCUAAGCUGCGGCUACCCCCGCAAGCAACCUUCCAAGUCCUUCGUGGCAAUGGUGCUUCCGUGGGGACCGUGCUCAUGUUCCGCUGCCCCUCCAACCACCAGAUGGUGGGGUCUGGGCUCCUCACCUGCACCUGGAAGGGGAGCAUCGCUGAGUGGUCUUCAGGGUCCCCAGUGUGCAAACUGGUGCCACCACACGAGACCUUUGGCUUCAAGGUGGCCGUGAUCGCCUCCAUUGUGAGCUGUGCCAUCAUCCUGCUCAUGUCCAUGGCCUUCCUCACCUGCUGCCUCCUCAAGUGCGUGAAGAAGAGCAAGCGGCGGCGCUCCAACAGGUCAGCCCAGCUGUGGUCCCAGCUGAAAGAUGAGGACUUGGAGACGGUGCAGGCCGCAUACCUUGGCCUCAAGCACUUCAACAAACCCGUGAGCGGGCCCAGCCAGGCGCACGACAACCACAGCUUCACCACAGACCAUGGUGAGAGCACCAGCAAGCUGGCCAGUGUGACCCGCAGCGUGGACAAGGACCCUGGGAUCCCCAGAGCUCUAAGCCUCAGUGGCUCCUCCAGCUCACCCCAAGCCCAGGUGAUGGUGCACAUGGCAAACCCCAGACAGCCCCUGCCUGCCUCUGGGCUGGCCACAGGAAUGCCACAACAGCCCGCAGCAUAUGCCCUAGGGUGACCACGCAGUGAGGCUGGUGCCCAUGCUCCACACUGGGAGGCCAGGCUGACCCCACCAGCCAGUCAGCUACAACUCCACAUCAACUCCACAUGCGCCCAGCUCGAGACUGAUGAGUGGAAUCAGCUUCCAGGUGUAGGGACCCCUUGAGGGGCCGAGCUGACAUCCAAGGCUGAGGACCCCAGUGGGGAGUGUUCUGUUCCGGCAUAUCCUGGCCGUAACGAUUUUUAUAGUUAUGGACUACUUGAAACCACUACUGAGGGUAAUUUACUAGCUGUGGCCUCCCACUAACUAGCAUUCCUUUAAAGAGACUGGGAAAUGUUUUAAGCAAAUCUAGUUUUGUAUAAUAAAAUAAGAAAAUAGCAAUAAACUUCUUUUCAGCAACUACA